GCUCCUUUCUCUCUCACGAUAAACUCAAUGGGGUUGUCUAUUUUUAACCUCCUGUUCUUUCCUUUUGGCAGAGUAAUCAGUGUGAGCUGAGCUCUUUCCCUGAAUGAAUCCAAGUAACCCUGGCCUUCUGAAAUGACCAGCAGACACACAACUGUCCAGAGGCUGCCCAAAGUAUAAACUCUGGUUCUAAAGUACCAUGUCCAGCCAAGGAAGUCCUAGUGUUGCGCUUUCUACGACGACAGUCAGUUCAGUUGCUGUGCAGGCUGGGGACUCCAAAAUCGUUAUAGCUGUCAUAAAGUGUGGCAAAUGGGUACAACUUCAACUGGCUGAAUCACAGCCCAAUCUUCUAGAAAUUGGCAGCAGUCAAGAUGAAACCAAAAAACUUCUUCAUGAUCAUGAACUUCUUUUGGCCAAGCUCAAGGCUUUGGAAGAUCGGGUAUGGGAACUCUUGCAGGAAGCAGACAAGACAGCUGAAGAGAACAAGGAUCAGAGUCAGGUCUAUGAUGCCAUGGCCGAGACUCUGGGUGAAGCAUGGGCAGCUCUGGUGUCCAUGCUUGAAAGAAGAACAGAGCUCCUUAGGUUGACUUCUGAAUUUUUUGAAAAUGCCUUAGAGUUUGCUAUUAAAAUAGACCAAGCUGAAGAUUUCCUCCAGAAUACUCAUGAGUUUGAGAGUGCUGAGUCCUUAAAAUCACUUCUUCAGCUUCAUGAACAUCAUACUAAAGAACUCUUGGAACGGUCUUUAGCCCUUUUAAACAAAAGUCAACAACUCACUGACUUCAUAGAAAAAUUCAAGUGUGAAGGACCUAAUGUGAAUCCUGAGUUGACUCAGGGAGCUCAUAGCAGCUGUCUGAAGGUUGACCGCCUUCUUGAACUUCUACAAGACAGGAGAAGACAACUAGACAAGUACUUGAAGCAACAGUGGCAAGAAUUGAGUCAAGUUCUGCAGAUAUGUCAGUGGGACCAACAAGAAAACCAGGUUACUUGUUGGUUUCAGAAAACUAUAAGAAAUUUACAGGAACAAAGUCUAGGUUCAUCACUUUCAGACAAUGAGGAUCGAAUUCAUAAGCAAGAGGAACUGAUAAUAAAAGCAAAGGAAUGGAAUUCUGCUGUUGAGAAGCUGAAGAGUGAGGCACUGAGAAUUCUGCUGUCAAAGGACUACGUGGAGAAAGAACACCUCCAGCUCUCUCACCAGAAACUCAGUCAGCUUCAAGAAGAAUUUGGUCAACUCAUGGUGGAAAGGAAUACCUGGUUAAAGAAGGCGAAUGAAUUUUUUAACAGUGCUAACAAGGCAUUUGAUGUACUUGGAAGAGUUGAAGCUUACCUUAAGCUCCUUAAAUCAGAGGGUUUAAGUCUGGCUGUUUUGGCAGUGAGGCAUGAGGAAUUACACAGAAAAAUUAAAGACUGCACAACUGAUGCUUUGCAAAAGGGACAAACCUUAAUCAGCCAAGUAGACUCCUGCAGCUCUCAGGUGUCCGGCAUCCAUGAGAUGAUGGGGUGCAUUAAGAGACGAGUGGAUCAUCUGACCGAACAGUGUUCAGCGCACAAGGAAUAUGCUCUUAAGAAACAACAACUAACAGCCUCAGUGGAGGGUUACCUACGGAAGGUGGAAAUGUCAAUUCAGAAAAUCAGUCCAGUACUUUCUAAUGCAAUGGAUGUUGGUUCUACCCGUUCUGAAUCAGAGAAGAUUUUGAAUAAAUAUCUGGAACUAGAUAUCCAAGCUAAGGAGACAUCACAUGAAUUAGAAGCAGCUGCAAAAACCAUGAUGGAGAAAAAUGAAUUUGUAUCUGAUGAAAUGGUAUCACUUUCCUCUAAAGCUAGAUGGCUAGCAGAAGAAUUAAACCUAUUUGGCCAAAGCAUUGACUAUAGAUCGCAAGUCCUGCAAACUUACGUGGCAUUUCUGAAGUCAUCAGAGGAGGUAGAGAUGCAGUUUCAGAGCUUAAAAGAAUUUUAUGAAACCGAAAUCCCUCAGAAGGAGCAGGAUGAUGCUAAAGCCAAGCAUUGUUCUGACUCGGCUGAGAAGCAGUGGCAGCUAUUUUUAAAGAAGAGUUUUAUAACACAAGAUCUAGGGCUUGAGUUCCUUAAUUUAAUAAAUAUGGCAAAAGAGAACGAGAUAUUAGAUGUGAAAAAUGAAGUGUACCUCAUGAAGAACACCAUGGAAAACCAGAAAGCAGAACGGGAAGAACUUAGCCUCCUUCGGCUGGCAUGGCAGCUUAAAGCCACGGAAAGCAAGCCUGGAAAACAGCAGUGGGCGGCAUUCAAAGAGCAACUUAAAAAGACUUCUCACAACUUAAAACUUCUUCAGGAAGCACUUAUGCCUGUGUCUGCACUUGACCUCGGAGGGAGCCUCCAGUUCAUUUUAGAUCUACGACAAAAAUGGAAUGACAUGAAGCCUCAGUUCCAGCAAUUGAAUGAUGAGGUUCAGUACAUUAUGAAAGAAUCAGAGGAGUUAACUGGCAGAGGAGCCCCUGUAAAAGAAAAGUCUCAACAACUGAAGGACCUUAUUCACUUCCAUCAAAAACAGAAAGAGAGAAUCCAGGAUUACGAGGAUAUCCUGUACAAGGUGGUCCAGUUCCAUCAAGUCAAGGAAGAGCUGGGACGUCUCAUCAAAUCAAGAGAGCUGGAGUUUGUAGAGCAGCCGAAGGAACUGGGUGAUGCCCAUGAUGUGCAGAUUCACCUCCGGUGCUCUCAGGAAAAGCAAGCCCGUGUAGACCAUCUCCACAGACUGGCCCUUUCCUUAGGAGUCGACAUCAUCUCAUCAGUGCAGCGGCCUCACUGCUCUAAUGUUUCUGCAAAGAACCUACAGCAGCAGCUGGAGCUCCUUGAGGAGGACAGCAUGAAGUGGCGUGCCAAAGCUGAGGAGUAUGGACGGACCCUGUCCCGUAGUGUGGAGUACUGCGCCAUGAGAGACGAGAUAAAUGAGCUCAAAGACUCAUUCAAAGAUAUCAAAAAGAAAUUCAAUAAUUUGAAGUUUAAUUACACUAAGAAAAAUGAAAAAUCUCGGAAUCUGAAGGCGCUUAAAUAUCAAAUUCAGCAAGUUGAUAUGUAUGCUGAAAAAAUGCAGGCUUUGAAAAGGAAAAUGGAAAAAGUUAGUAAUAAAACCUCUGAUUCUUUCUUAAAUUAUCCAAGUGAUAAAGUUAAUGUCCUUUUGGAAGUCAUGAAGGAUUUGCAAAAACAUGUGGAUGACUUUGACAAAGUUGUGACAGAUUACAAGAAGAAUUUGGACCUGACUGAGCAUUUCCAGGAGGUGAUAGAAGAGUGUCAUUUUUGGUACGAAGAUGCAAGUGCCACAGUUGUAAGAGUUGGAAAAUAUUCCACAGAGUGCAAGACAAAGGAAGCUGUGAAAAUUCUCCACCAGCAGUUUAAUAAGUUUAUUGCACCCUCAGUGCCGCAGCAAGAAGAAAGGAUUCAGGAGGCCACUGACCUUGCUCAGCACUUAUAUGGUUUGGAAGAAGGACAGAAAUAUAUUGAGAAAAUAGUGACAAAACACAAAGAGGUUCUUGAAUCUGUGACUGAAUUAUGUGAGUCCCUCACAGAGCUCGAAGAAAAACUGAAGCAGGGAGAUGUUUUAAAGAUGAAUCCGAAUUUGGAAGACUUCCAUUAUGAUUACAUUGACUUGCUAAAGGAACCAGCAAAAAAUAAGCAGACAAUAUUCAAUGAAGAAAGGAAUAAGGGGCAGGUGCAGGUGGCAGAUCUUUUGGGCAUCAAUGGAACAGGGGAAGAGCGACUACCACAAGACCUGAAGGUGUCCACUGACAAGGAGGGUGGCGUCCAGGACCUGCUCCUGCCUGAAGACAUGCUCUCAGGGGAAGAAUAUGAGUGUGUCUCACCUGAUGACAUCUCCUUGCCUCCUCUCCCAGGAAGCCCUGAGUCCCCUCUUGCACCAUCUGACAUGGAGGUGGAAGAGCCUGUCAGCUCCUCCCUCAGCCUUCACAUAAGCAGCUAUGGGGUGCAGGCUGGGACCAGCAGCCCAGGGGAUGCCCAGGAAUCUGUUCUUCCACCACCUGUUGCCUUUGCGGAUGCAUGCAAUGAUAAGAGAGAAACAUUUUCAAGUCAUUUUGAGAGGCCUUACCUCCAGUUCAAAGCUGAGCCCCCACUAACCUCCAGAGGAUUCGUGGAAAAGAGUACUGCCUUACACAGAAUCAGUGCUGAACAUCCAGAGAGCAUGAUGAGUGAAGUGCAUGAGAGAGCUUUACAGCAGCACCCUCAGGCUCAGGGUGGUUUGCUAGAAACACGGGAGAAAAUGCAUGCUGAUAAUAACUUCACUAAAACCCAAGAUAGGCUGCAUGCUUCCUCUGAUGCAUUCUCGGGCCUCAGGUUUCAAUCAGGCACCAGCAGGGGCUAUCAGAGGCAAAUGGUUCCUCGAGAAGAGAUUAAAAGCACAUCAGCAAAGAGCAGCGUGGUCAGCCUAGCUGACCAGGCACCUAAUUUCUCCAGGCUCCUGUCUAAUGUAACUGUCAUGGAAGGUUCUCCAGUGACUUUGGAAGUUGAAGUAACAGGAUUUCCAGAGCCUACACUGACAUGGGGUAGCUGGAUAUCUGAAUUUUCAUAUGCAAUAUUCCAAUUUUUAAAGGAUUUCAAAAAAUUCAGUUUUCCAAAAACAUUGUCUGAGCCAGUCAAAGCAAUUCUCUCGCCACCAGUUGCCAACUUCUGCUUGAAAGAUAAACAGCGCAUAAUACCAGCUACUCAGGAGGCUGAGGCAGGCAGAUUGCUUGAAACCAGGAGUUCAAGACCAGCCUGGGUACAAGAAGGGCCAGAAAUUGUCUGCAGAUGGGCACUUACAGGUUUUACACAAGGAGACAAGGCAUUCGGUGUUCAUUCCAAAGGUAUGCAAGGCAGACGCAGGCCUCUAUGUGGCUCGGGCCCAAAACUCUAGCGGCGCUCUCUCUUCCAAUGUCAUCCUCCACGUGACAGGUAACUGCAGGCUGCCAAUCACAAGAGUAAACUGGAUAACCCUGUGUGUCGUCUAUGUUAGUGUGUCCCUAAUGUACUGGCUCCUCACACAAUAACUGUGGUGUUGGCACCAAUGGACAUCAUUCUCAUGUGCCUAAAGAAAAGUGCCGCCGUUUAUCUUCCUGCACCUCCUGCAAAGCAUCUCCCACCAAGUGUAUCUCCAGUCUGAUCACCAUACUUGUUUGGCUAAUACCACUGCUAGGUGAAAUAAUCAAAUUUUCUGGAGCGUUUAAUAUAUUUGAGAAGCUUGGUAAAUUAUCUGUAGUGGAUAAGAACAGAUUUUUGUACUCUAGAAACAGAUGUUUUCAACAUAAUAUGCAGCAAAAUUAUUCUAUGCCUAUUCCCUCCUAAUUUAAGGGCGUGCAGAUGAAGGCUGACAUCGGCAUAGAAAUGUGCUAAAUUUCAAAUAUGGUUGUUCAAUAAUAUAUUUUUAAUUGUAUUUUAAAACAUCCCUUUGUAGGGAAUAUCAGUAGAACUAUUGAAUUGAUGUUGUAUUUUUGCAUUAGCUGUCCUUUAAUUUUGCUUUCCAUGUCUUGAUCUUGUUACCGAAAUGCAUUCUGUGUAAUUUCAACGUAGACUACGUUCCUGAGUCUGAUGAUGUCAUUGUAAAUAAUCAUUCCUCAUGUUGCUCUCACGGGUUUGACAUUGGAGGAUAGAUGUGCCAUCAACUUUAAAUAGAGUUUCCAUCUUUUGUCAGCUCUGCAUGUCAUACAGCAAGAUGGAACACAGGUUGCAAGAAAGAACCAACGUUAUUCCUGACAUUCUAUUGAUGUGUUUUGAGCAGCAAUGUGUAACCAGGUGUUUCUGCUUCUAAUCUUGAUUCUGCUGAUGACCAUUUUUAUACUUUAUGGCAAAGCCUCAUUGCCUCAGUUUCCUGUCUGGAAAAUGAGUUCAUCAUCUACCUCUUGGGCAAUUGAGAGUUUUCAUUUUGUGUCUUUUAAACAUCUGGAAAAUGGAAAACACUGAGGGCUAAGGAUAAUGAUAUUGUUUAAUGUAAUUUGUCAUCAGACCGGCCUCCUGCUCACUAUUUCUUUUUUUUUAGAUGCUGUUUUUUUAGAAUAUUAAAUUAAAGGAGUGCUGUUAAUAUGUAAUCUUCAACUAGUUCCAUGGAGGAAAGUGAUGUUUUAUGAAUUAGAGCUUAAAUUCCUAUCUAAUUUCUGAAGACUGCAUUCUUUUCAAAGACUUGAAAUUAAACUCAGGAGGAUACAUUUUGUUUGUUCUAGGGGGAAACGUAAUAGAAUGGUAUGAGAUGAAUUCUAUCCUUUUACAAUAAUUAUUACUAUAAUAUUGAAGUAUUCUAUGCCUUUCUGAAACACUUUAUUCAGAAAAGAUCAUUUUUUGGCUUCCUUUUAAAAAUAAGCUUGAAGUAGGGAAGCAUUUGCUUCUUAGAUUUUAAAUGUAGUCUUAUUAUGCUGAGGAAAAUCUUUAGUUGAAAGAAUAAUUCAUUACAGAUUUUUGAUGAAGGGAAGAAAUUAAUUAUGUUGCUGGAAGACUGUCUACAAAUAAUCAAAAUAUUUAAAUGUAAUGUAUUCAAGUUGUUAUUAAAAAGUUACUGAAUGUUAUCUGAAGAUGUGAAAUGUGUAGUCAAGUAAAAAGUUGGCGUAUACUUUCUUGGGCUGCAUAUCCAAUUUAAUUAAAAAAUUAAAUCUCAGUUUCCUUCUAAAUUUUGAUAGAACUAUAUUAAAAGCUUGUAUACACAGCAUUCUAGGAAAUUUCUCUUAACUAUCUUUUUUUUGUUUUUUUUGUUUUUUUUUUUUUUUUUUGAGAAAGAGUCUUGCUCUCUUGCCCAGUGCAGUGGUGCCAUCUUGGCUCACUGCAACCUCCACCUCCGGGUUCAAGCAAUUCUCCUGCUUCAGCCUCCUGAGUAGCUAGGAUUACAGGCAUGCCUACCUAAUAUUUACAUUUUUAGUAGAAACCAGGUUUCACCAUGUUGGCCAGGCUGGGCCUCAGCCUCCCAAAGUGCCAGGAUUACAGGUAUGAGCCACCAUAGCCGGCCUCUUGUAUCCUUUUUGUCCAAUUUCAAAUAAUGUGUGAAUCUUGCCUAACUGCUGUUGCCCACGUUGAAGCUAAAGAGUAAAAACCUAUUCAUGAACAAAGAAGGCAGGUGAGACCCGGUAACAAACUGUCUCUCUUCCCACUUUCUCUUUCUUAUUAAUUUGGCAGGAUCUCCCUUCCCAUUUUGUCAACAUGGUUGAAUUUGUGUGUUGGGGUUGUUAGGGCAUGGGAAUUCCUGGUUUGCUUUCUCUAUUGCAUGCUUGUUCAUGUUAACUCUUUGGGGAGCAGAAUGAGAUACAUAUGCAUCCAUGGUUAUGAUGGAAAAAAGCAUGCAAAAUCCAUUUUUAGAGAGAGAGAGAAAGAGAAAGGUGGGGGUGGGGGAGCACAAAGAUCAGAAGAGUACUAUGCUGAUAUUCAAGAUAUAGUACAGAUAGCUUUCUGUGUACCUAUCCAUCUACCUAUUCAUCUGGGCUAUUGAUUGACUCCCACAGCAGUAAAGAAUAAUUACGCAGUUAUUCUUCUGGUUAUGUUUUAAUUUCAAAAAGUUAAGUGUGAUUUUCCUUUUUGCUGGGAUUUCUGUCUUGAGCAAAUAAUUAUUCUUAUGAAAGUAUCAAUUGCAGUUACUGGUUAAAAAUGUAAGACCUAGGAAAUUUAAGUGUUGUUUCUAUUUUAAGGUAUAUACAUAAUUUAUAACCAUUUACUUCUAGAGAAAAUCCUGAAUGGUUAGUAAUAUCAAAACAUUUUCAACAAGAAAACUAAAAUGAAAAGAAAGUUUAAAAAUUACAUGUGUUACAGCUCUUUUAGAAUUUGUCUAGCAGGUUUUCUGGUGAAAAUUAAACUCAAGAUUUUCACCAGAAAACGUUUUAAAACUUCUAAACUCUUAAACAAAUUAUAAAUACUUGAUACUUUGAAGAACUGCAAAACAAAAUGUUUUUAAGUUUUCAUAAGGCAAAAUCAUUGAGUUUUCCAGCUUUGAUUUUCCAAUAAAAGGAUGUAUAAAUAUUUGGUGGUAGUUUUUCACACUCAAUUCCAAGAGAAAUUUACUGUAGGAAUCUGUACAUUUGAAUCUCUGAAUAUUCUAUGAUAUUUAAAAUAUUUGAACAAGAUGCAGAAAAUUUUUUAGCUAUAUUAAUCAAUAAUGGUAACCUCUAUCACUCAUAAUCAAGACACAUACUUAAAAUAGAUGACUACAAGACCCUUCUAACUGCUUUGCUCAAAUUUAAAUUUCCUCAAGUAGUUCAUAGACCCUUUACAACCUGGCCUCCCCUCUCUGGCCUCGGUUUGAUCCCCUCCUAUUACCCCCAACCCCUAGUAAAGUGACAUUUAACUUCAGGGUUUUAACAUAUCAUGCUCUUCUCUCCAGCCCUUUCUUCCUAUAACUCUCUUACUAUCUUCACCACCCUAUCUUCAUGUGACUUAACUCUUGCUUAUGUUCCAGUUCUGCUGAGACACAACUUCCCCUGGGAAGCCUCCUGACCCAUCAAGUCCAGAGUAGAUGGUCCUGCCAUGUGCACUGUCAGCACCUGCACUGCCCAGCCACGCCCCUGAAUAUACACAAAGGAAUCGCAGGUUUGAGCAUCAGUCUCCUCUGGCUAGGCUGUAAGAACCUUAUCAGCAGGAUUCAUGACAGCCCUGUUGUCAUUGUAUUGCCAGUACCUAAGACACAGUCACACUCAGUAAACUCUUUUGAAUUGAAUUGUUGCCAAAGGUAAACAAAGAUAAACCUAGCUUGUUUUUCUCCCCUUUUUAGAGGGAGGAGAGGGGAAAUGUAAAAAGACAAAGAUGAUUCUCCCUUCUUAUAGACAGGAGUCAAUCCGAAUCAGGCCCUAACAAUGAAGCACUCAUGAAAAUCUCUCACCUCAUCUGCAAAACUUGUGUGAGAACCCUCCAGACCCUCUGGGCUAGACCCUGAUUGAAAAUUUGAAUUUAAAAAUAGAUGCUGGCUCCACGGACUAAAAUAAUAGUAAGGAGGAAAGAGGAAAGGUCCAGGAUUGUUGUUCCUGGAUCAAUAUUGUUCCAACAUUUUAAAGUGUUCCAACAUUUUAAAACAUAUGUACUUAGGCAUAAAUCAUCAUCCGGUAUGAGGAACUGGAUGCCUCCACUCUCUAUGACUAAAUCCAAACUGUCAAAACCAGAAUUUAUGUACUUCUUUAGAACACUACGUAAAUGAUCAAUAUUUAAUUGUAGCUGGGGCUCAGUAGUCUGGGCUGUGAACAGAUCUUAUUUGAAACCAGUAUUUCAUACAAACUUGUAAAUAUAAAGAAAGCCAAAUCCAAGAACUUAAGAGUAUUUGAAUUCCAAAUGAAGAAAGGAAAGAAUAUCUUAUUUUGUUCUGCUUUAUGUUUGUCUUUAUUCAUGACCAUUUCUUACUAAAAAUCACCAUCUGAAGCUUUUGAAACUCCUGUUGUAUGCACAGCAUUUUAAGUGCAGCCAUGAAAUAAGUUAGUUGAAACAAAAUAAAAUAUCUCCUUCCAGUA